GAGAGGGCUAGCGAAGCCGAAGGGAGCGCGGCUAAGAGUGCCGCACCGCCUCACAACCUGGGAACCGGAGAGUAGGGGCCGUCGGCUGGCAAGAACCCGCCGUGCCUCCUCGGCAAGGGCCAUCCGGUGCCACCCAUGUCGCACUAGAGCAGAAGAGGGUGAGUCCUGGAACUGCAACCUGCACAGAGCUGCUCUGUACUGUCCCUGGUGGUCGCCGCCAUGACCUGGUUGGUGCUGCUGGGGACACUGCUCUGCAUGCUGCGCGUUGGGUUAGGCACCCCGGACUCCGAGGGUUUCCCGCCCCGUGCGCUCCACAACUGCCCCUACAAAUGUAUCUGCGCUGCCGACCUGCUAAGCUGCACUGGCCUAGGGCUGCAGGACGUGCCAGCCGAGUUACCUGCCGCUACUGCGGACCUCGACCUGAGCCACAACGCGCUCCAGCGCCUGCGCCCCGGCUGGUUGGCGCCCCUCUUCCAGCUGCGCGCCCUGCACCUAGACCACAACGAACUAGAUGCGCUGGGUCGCGGCGUCUUCGUCAACGCCAGCGGCCUGAGGCUGCUCGAUCUAUCAUCUAACACGUUGCGGGCGCUUGGCCGCCACGACCUCGACGGGCUGGGGGCGCUGGAGAAGCUGCUUCUGUUCAAUAACCGCUUGGUGCACUUGGACGAGCAUGCCUUCCACGGCCUGCGCGCGCUCAGCCAUCUCUACCUGGGCUGCAACGAACUCGCCUCGUUCUCCUUCGACCACCUGCACGGUCUGAGCGCCACCCACCUGCUUACUCUGGACCUCUCCUCCAACCGGCUGGGACACAUCUCCGUACCUGAGCUGGCCGCGCUGCCGGCCUUCCUCAAGAACGGCCUCUACUUGCACAACAACCCUUUGCCUUGCGACUGCCGCCUCUACCACCUGCUACAGCGCUGGCACCAGCGGGGCCUGAGCGCCGUGCGCGACUUUGCGCGCGAGUACGUAUGCUUGGCCUUCAAGGUACCCGCGUCCCGCGUGCGCUUCUUCCAGCACAGCCGCGUCUUUGAGAACUGCUCGUCGGCCCCAGCUCUUGGCCUAGAGCGGCCGGAAGAGCACCUGUACGCGCUGGUGGGUCGGUCCCUGAGGCUUUACUGCAACACCAGCGUCCCGGCCAUGCGCAUUGCCUGGGUUUCGCCGCAGCAGGAGCUUCUCAGGGCGCCAGGAUCCCGCGAUGGCAGCAUCGCGGUGCUGGCCGACGGCAGCUUGGCCAUAGGCAACGUACAGGAGCAGCAUGCGGGACUCUUCGUGUGCCUGGCCACUGGGCCCCGCCUGCACCACAACCAGACGCACGAGUACAACGUGAGCGUGCACUUUCCGCGCCCAGAGCCCGAGGCUUUCAACACAGGCUUCACCACACUGCUGGGCUGUGCCGUGGGCCUUGUGCUCGUGCUGCUCUACCUGUUCGCCCCACCCUGCCGCUGCUGCCGCCGUGCCUGCCGCUGCCGCCGCUGGCCCCAAACACCCAGCCCGCUCCAAGAGCUGAGCGCACAGUCCUCAGUACUCAGCACCACACCGCCAGACGCACCCAGCCGCAAGGCCAGCGUCCACAAGCACGUAGUCUUUCUGGAGCCAGGCCGGAGGGGCCUCAAUGGCCGCGUGCAGCUGGCAGUAGCUGAGGAAUUCGAUCUCUACAACCCUGGAGGCCUGCAGCUGAAGGCUGGCUCUGAGUCCGCCAGCUCCAUAGGCUCCGAGGGUCCCAUGACAACCUAGACUGCCCAGGGCUCCCCCACCCAGGCCCCCACCCUCUUGCUGCUCGCCCUGCUCCCUGCUUCGGUCCAGAGAACUGGCAGAUACUGGUGGGAAGCACUGUGCCUGGCCCCCCAGCUUCCUGUAUGGGCCUCGAAACACAAUGGGCCUUCUCGCUCACUGGUAGAGACAGGGGUUGUGGUCCCCAACCUGCCUUCUGCUCUGCCCCUGCACAGGACCCAAAGGCCCCAGGCCCUGCAAGGUGUGCUAGUUCCUGCUUUCCCGCGGACUUCCUAGUGCCCAAAUGCCCUGUGAGGCUGAGAGACCCAGGCCCCUGUGGCUUUCAACACAGCACAGCUGUGGAAGUGGCUGUGUUCUUCUACAGCCUGUGGAAGAACCCCUGUAGCAGAGCCUCCCGUCCACCCUCAGGGGCUGAGACAGCUCUCGAGGAGUGGUGCUCAAGAGCUGACGCAGGGCCACCUCCCCUUCCCAAGGGGGUGGGAGGGAGUGGGCCCACAGGGAAAAGAAGGCGGCUCUGAAGGAAGAUCUCGCCCACACCCCAGGACAGAAAGAGGAAACAAGCCCGCCCUCUGGUGAAAUGGGACUCCCUCCAUCCACCAACACCCAACCUCCUGAAAGCUUCACAACUUCACGCAGAGUCCGGUGGGCAGGCACCAGGCAGGAAAGGCUCCUCAAGAGGUUCCUGGUGGUCUGGCCUAAGCCCCAGCCAGAGGCCCUGCUCUCUCUGGCCUGGGGCAUCCACCCGUUGUUCUGAAGGCAGAGCCCAUUCUGUGGGCUCACAAGACACAGUGAAGGGGAUCAUGGCCUGCACCCCUGCUUUUCAGCAGUAAAAAGCCCGAAAAGCCUGGCGAGCAUGGCCGAGCUGGGAGGGCCGAGCCGGAACUCCACGUCCCUCGAGAGCAGGAGCCUCUUAAGGGCUGGCACUGGUCUCAGCCUAAUGGCUGAGGCGGUACCCUGGCUUCAUAUGCAUCUCACUGCUCCCACUGCAGGGGGGCAGGGAAGGGGGGUCUGGGAGCCCUUCAUGUGUGGGGGCCGAGCUGGGGGCCCCCAUGGCCAUCCUGGACCUCGCUGCUCCAGAGUUUAAUAAAGGUAGCACAUGCUUAUUGCUAGAGCCUUUGCAGACAA